CUCACGGAGCUCGUAGUUUCCCGGACGGGCCGCUCCCGGCCUCGCGGCCUCGCCUCCCCACACUACAACUCCCACGGGGCAGCGGGCGCGGCUCCCCGUACCCACCAGCUGGCCGGGCAGGGCAGCCACUUCGCGGUCGGGCCCGCCGGCUGCGGGCACCCGCGCGACGGGCGGGAAGAUGGCGGACGUGGUCGUGGGUAAAGACAAGGGCGGGGAGCAGCGGCUCAUCUCGCUGCCUCUAUCCCGCAUCCGGGUCAUCAUGAAGAGCUCCCCCGAGGUGUCCAGCAUCAACCAGGAGGCGUUGGUGCUCACGGCCAAGGCCACGGAGCUCUUUGUUCAAUGCCUAGCCACCUAUUCCUACAGACACGGCAGUGGAAAGGAAAAGAAAGUACUGACUUACAGUGAUUUAGCAAACACUGCACAGCAAUCAGAAACUUUUCAGUUUCUUGCAGAUAUAUUACCAAAGAAGAUUUUAGCUAGUAAAUACCUGAAAAUGCUUAAAGAGGAAAAGAGGGAAGAAGAUGAGGAGAAUGACAAUGAUAAUGAAAGUGACCAUGAUGAAGCUGACUCCUAAACCAAAAGUGCUUUAAAAACCAGCCUGGCGAGGACAGCCCUGGACCCACUCCACUGUCUCUAAGUAAACACAGCACUGCCCGCUUUUAGCGUCUUCACUUCUUCACAGAGUUCCAGUGUGUGGUAUUCUUUCGAGGUAUUCUUUCCAGGCCGAGAUUGAGCACCUCAUGUACCUACGCCACAGACAGCCAGAGGGAAAGCGACCCAGACAGCAGCCCCUCCUCGACAGGCCCACCCUGCAGCUCAGGCACCAAGAAAACAGCCGAUACUGGCAGCCAUUGCAGCUCCAAACUGCAGAGGCAAGGCCAAUUUUAACUUUUCAAUUUACAGUCGAUUUUGAAGAGCUUCUACAUAUCGGUUAUGUAAAUUCAUAUAUGUAUAUUUUGGAAUCAGUUCUUAUAAACAGCUCGAUUCAGUUUUAGCUAAAUUUAUAGUUUAGGUAGUAUGUUACAUUUGAAUUUUUGUCUUAAGAAAAGUUGACUGUUCAGAUAUUUUUCUACUGUAAAGAAAUAUACUUUUCUAUUAAAGAUCUGUACAUAUUUUUACAGUAAAAUGCUUUAUGGAACUAGUUUUAGAGCCCUCUAUGGCUUUAAGGCCUUGCUUACUGCCUGCAAAUUUUGAGAAAUUUAAAAAUAAGCAUUCUAACACUUUUAUUCCCACAGAAAAAUUCCAAGUCAAAUUAUCAAAUCAAAUACAAAAAUAAGUCUUACCUCUUGUAUAAGCAUGUUGUACUAAAAAAAAAUUUUGAAACAUUUUGUAUAUUGGAGAUCUCUCUCAUCUUACUGUUCUUUGCUUUAAAUUCCUGGCACUUCUUUUUACUGUCUAUAAGAGAAAACCUAUCAUAAGCCCAAUUUUUUUUUUCCACUUAGGGUAAAUGUUUGGCUCCUCUCAUUUCAUUAUCUUUUUUUUUUUUUUUUUAAAGACAGAUUCUCACUCAGUUGCCCAGGCUGGAUUGCGGUGGCGCUGUCUCAGCUCACUGCAACCUCCGCCUCCCAGGUUCAAGUGAUUCUCCUGCCUCAUCCUCCUGAGUAGCUGGGAUUACAGGCGUGUGCCACCAUGCCCAACCUAUUUUUGUAUUUUUUAGUAGAGACGGGGUUCACCAUGUUGGCCAGGCUUGUCUCAAACUCCUAACCUCAACUGAUCCACCUGCCUCAGCCUCCCAAAGUGCCGCCGGGAUUACAGGCGUGAGCCACCAUGCCUGGCCUUCAUUAUCUCUUUUUUAAAAAUGAAAAAGUUUAUAAUUUACAUUCAGUAAAAUCACCCUUUUUAGUGUCUAGUCUGUGAAUUUUGACAAAUGCAUGGUUUUGUAACCAAUCGAUAGGACAGUUCUGCCACCCAGGACAUUCCCCUCUGUUCCUCUGUUCCUCUCUUCUCCUGCCCCCUAGCAACCACUGGUGUUUUCUGUCCCUCUUGUUCAUUGACAUUUAUUUUAAAAUAAAAUAUUUUAAAAUCUACUUUUUGGUGUACAGUUCUGAGUUUUGGCAAAUGCAGUCAAGUCACUACCACCACCACAAUUAACAGCUAUAUCACCCUCCAGUAAAUUCCCUGUGGUCAGCUCCUUCCCCACCUUUUACCGUGGCAACCGUCAAGCUAUUCUCUGUCCCUAUACCAGGUGUCAUCAAAUUUUUUUCUGGAAAGGGCCAUGCAGUAAAUAGUUCAAGCUUUGUGGGCUUUUAUAGUCUCUGUUGCUGCUGCUGAACUCAGCUGUUGUAGCACGAAAGCAGCCAGGUAAUUACUAGAUGAAGGAAUGCAGGUGGCUGUGUUUCAAUAGAGCUUUAUUUCUGCAAACUGAAACUUGAGUUUUGUGUAAUUUUCAUGUGUCAUGAAAUACUGUUUUCUCCAACCAUUUAAUAAUGUAAAUACUUGCUAGCUUAUGUGCCAUUAAAAAAUGACUUGAUUUGGCUUACA